GUGAAUGUAAAGAGAUCCAGGGCUCUUGGAGAGGGACAAGUGAGAGCCAGCCAAAAAGGAAAAAGCAAAGGCAGAAACGGCAUCAGGAGAGACAGAGAUGUGAAGGAGGGAAGGAGCAGGAGAGCAGGAAGGAAACGCAGGAGGAGGGAGCAGCAUCUCCUGUGAACACAGAGGAGCACCUGUUUGCUGUUAAAAUCGAUCUCCCUCGGCACCCUGAGCAAUGGAUAUAAUAUUUGGCAGGAAUAGGAAAGAACAGCUGGAGCCUGUGAGGGCCAAAGUGACAGGCAAGAUUCCAGCAUGGCUGCAGGGAACCCUGCUCCGCAAUGGGCCUGGGAUGCACACAGUUGGGGAGUCCAGAUACAACCAUUGGUUCGACGGCCUUGCCCUGCUCCACAGCUUCACCAUCAGAGACGGUGAAGUCUAUUACAGGAGCAAAUACCUGAGAAGCGAUACCUACAACACCAAUAUUGAGGCAAACAGGAUUGUGGUGUCUGAGUUUGGAACAAUGGCCUAUCCGGACCCCUGCAAAAACAUAUUUUCCAAAGCUUUCUCCUACUUGUCUCACACCAUCCCCGAUUUCACCGACAACUGCCUGAUCAACAUCAUGAAGUGCGGAGAAGACUUCUACGCGACCUCAGAGACCAAUUACAUCAGGAAAAUCAACCCACAGACUCUGGAAACCCUGGAGAAGGUUGAUUAUCGUAAAUACGUGGCGGUAAAUCUGGCAACGUCACAUCCCCAUUAUGAUGAGGCUGGAAAUGUUCUAAACAUGGGCACAUCCAUUGUGGAAAAGGGGAAGACAAAGUAUGUGAUUUUUAAGAUCCCUGCCACAGUACCAGAGGGCAAGAAGCAGGGGAAGAGCCCCUGGAAGCACACAGAGGUGUUCUGCUCCAUCCCAUCCCGCUCCCUGCUCUCCCCAAGCUACUACCACAGCUUUGGAGUCACCGAGAACUAUGUCAUCUUCCUUGAGCAGCCUUUCAGGUUGGAUAUUCUCAAGAUGGCAACCGCAUACAUCCGGAGAAUGAGCUGGGCCUCCUGCCUGGCUUUCCACAGGGAGGAGAAGACUUAUAUCCACAUCAUCGACCAAAGGACCAGGCAGCCUGUGCAGACCAAGUUUUACACAGACGCCAUGGUGGUCUUCCAUCACGUCAACGCCUACGAAGAGGACGGCUGCAUCGUGUUUGACGUCAUUGCCUACGAGGACAACAGCCUCUACCAGCUCUUCUACCUGGCCAACCUGAACCAGGACUUCAAGGAGAACUCCAGGCUCACCUCGGUCCCCACCCUCAGGAGGUUUGCCGUGCCCCUCCACGUGGACAAGAAUGCAGAAGUGGGCACAAAUUUAAUCAAAGUGGCAUCUACAACAGCCACGGCCCUGAAGGAAGAAGAUGGCCAAGUCUACUGCCAGCCGGAAUUUCUUUAUGAAGGCUUAGAGCUUCCACGGGUCAAUUAUGCUCACAAUGGAAAGCAAUACCGAUAUGUCUUUGCUACAGGAGUUCAGUGGAGUCCAAUCCCAACCAAG